CGUCGUCACUUCCUGCCGAUGCCGGUGUGGACGCUGUGAAUCGUGGCUGGCCCGGUUCUCCGCUUCUCCCCAUCCCCUACUUUCCUCCCUCCCUCCCUUUCCCUCCCUCGUCGACUGUUGCUUGCUGGUCGCAGACUCCCUGACCCCUCCCUCACCCCUCCCUAACCUCGGUGCCACCGGAUUGCCCUUCUUUUCCUGUUGCCCAGCCCAGCCCUAGUGUCAGGGCGGGGGCCUGGAGCAGCCCGAGGCACUGCAGCAGAAGAGAGAAAAGACAACGACGACCCUCAGCUCGCCAGUCCGGUCGCUGGCUUCGCCGCCGCCAUGGCAAUGAGACAGACGCCGCUCACCUGCUCUGGCCACACGCGACCCGUGGUUGAUUUGGCCUUCAGUGGCAUCACGCCUUAUGGGUAUUUCUUAAUCAGCGCUUGCAAAGAUGGUAAACCUAUGCUACGCCAGGGAGAUACAGGAGACUGGAUUGGAACAUUUUUGGGUCAUAAAGGUGCUGUUUGGGGUGCAACACUGAAUAAGGAUGCCACCAAAGCAGCUACAGCAGCUGCAGAUUUCACAGCCAAAGUGUGGGAUGCUGUCUCAGGAGAUGAAUUGAUGACCCUGGCUCAUAAACACAUUGUCAAGACUGUGGAUUUCACGCAGGAUAGUAAUUAUUUGUUAACCGGGGGACAGGAUAAACUGUUACGCAUAUAUGACUUGAACAAACCUGAAGCAGAACCUAAGGAAAUUAGUGGUCAUACUUCUGGUAUAAAAAAAGCUCUGUGGUGCAGUGAGGAUAAACAGAUUCUUUCUGCUGAUGACAAAACUGUUCGACUUUGGGAUCAUGCUACUAUGACAGAAGUGAAAUCUCUAAAUUUUAAUAUGUCUGUUAGUAGUAUGGAAUAUAUUCCUGAGGGAGAGAUUUUGGUUAUAACUUAUGGACGAUCUAUUGCUUUUCAUAGUGCAGUAAGUUUGGACCCAAUUAAAUCCUUUGAAGCUCCUGCAACCAUCAAUUCUGCAUCUCUUCAUCCUGAGAAAGAAUUUCUUGUUGCAGGCGGUGAAGAUUUUAAACUUUAUAAGUAUGAUUAUAAUAGUGGAGAAGAAUUAGAAUCCUACAAGGGACACUUUGGUCCUAUUCACUGUGUGAGAUUUAGUCCUGAUGGAGAACUCUAUGCCAGUGGUUCAGAAGAUGGAACAUUGAGACUAUGGCAAACUGUGGUAGGAAAAACGUAUGGCCUUUGGAAAUGUGUGCUUCCUGAAGAAGAUAGUGGUGAGCUGGCAAAGCCAAAGAUUGGUUUUCCAGAGACAACAGAAGAGGAGCUAGAAGAAAUUGCUUCAGAGAAUUCAGAUUGCAUCUUUCCUUCAGCUCCUGAUGUUAAGGCCUGAGCGUCAAUCAUAUGUGCAGUUAGUAUACAACUGACUAAAACAAGCAAGCAGAGAAAAGCAUCAGCCUUCCAGAGUUACUGUCUGCUUAAGGCAGAAACAGCAGUAAAUAAUGAGGAAAAUGAAUUAGCUCCAGUGCUGGAACAACUAACUAACUUGGUGUUACCUGUAAGUGAAAACUCAAGUGUCAGAUGAAGGGAGGUGGAGUUAUCCUCUUAUAGUACAGUGGCCUGUUAUCUUUUUAAUGAAUAUAUACAAGCCAACAUCCAAUUUCUAUUAUUACAAUUAGGGUUCUUGUAGCUGUUUAUGUUAAUAUGGAGAAGAAAACUAUAUUGGCUGAUUUUUUCUGAUCUUAAAGCAGAAUGCCUUUUCUUUUUUUGCUUCAGUUGUAAAGAAGAGGGAAUACAUGAUAAAGUAACUGGUUUGAUUUCUCGUUCAUUGUACACUGCCUCUGAACAUCUAAUUGUUUUUAGUUGUCUAAAUAAAAUGCCUCUAAAACAAAA